GAUUUUCAGCUGGCCUGGCCAGUGUCUGUUUCAUUGUAAUUUCUUUGUGGAAGCCUCAGUUGUCUUUCCCAUCUCGGGAUGUGGCCCCGAGCUCCCUGCACAGACGUGGAAGGUGCAUGGGCUCUGGUCGGGAAGCUGUUUGCCUCAUCUCAUUUCCGUCGCCCUAGGGGAGGUCUUUCGAGUUGGUCUGCAGGUUGCCCUGGUUCUUUCCAGUGUCUGUGUGGGGCUCUCUUGCACAGACGCCUUCUGGUUUCUUCAGCUUCUCUGUCUGGACAGUUGAGACACUGAGGGUGGCAGAGCCAGGCCCUGGCUGUGGCUCUAGCCUGUCCACCCACUGUGCUUGGAGGGAAGGUGUCUGCAGACGGGACCAGCCCUCGGCCCCAGAGGGGAUGACAUGGUGUGAAUGUGCUGUGGACGGGGACCUGAGGCACUGAGCCCGUCUCAGCCCUCCCUCCCCACUGGGACUCUGGGAACUGCACAUUCUCCCACAGGGAGGGGUCACCCCGGGCUCUCACCUGACUGUCGCCUCCUGGUCUCCUCCUGCCCGGCGUGGUCCUUGCCAGGUGGUGGGUCCCAGUACCUGGUAGCGGAGGGGGCUUGAGGGGGAUGCCACCCCUUUGCCCUCUGGCUGCCCUCCCUCCCUGCCCCUCCCACUGGCUGGUGCCAGGCUGCCUGGGGGCUCCGCUUCUAUGCCAAGGGCUUCUGGGGGAGGCAGGGCCACUUAUCAUGGCAUCGUGUUGUCCUCGAGUUUUUGCAAAAUCUGAGUGUGUGGGGUGUAGGUGUCUCAGAGGGCAGGGUUUGUGUUCCAGGAGAGGAGAGGUGAGAUCACCAUGCCUCACCACCGAGGGUGGGGCAGUCGCCUGCCCGUGUGUGCCAGGGGCUUUUUAUACUGCACCCCUCAGCCUUCCAGGUCUUGUUGGGGUUGGUGUGUUUCUGCCAGGUAGCGGAGCUGGAGGCAAACUGCACCCUCAGGGCCUGUAGUGACCACUGGCAUUCAGUGAGCACAUGCUGGCACCAGGUGCAGCCCCAGAGCUUUAACCACAUUGGCCGGGAUUUCCCUGGCAGCAGCAAGAGGGCUUCUGGGCUGGGCCUUGGACGGCUCUGCCGUGGCUCGUGGGCUGGUGCCAAGCAGAGCCUGGGGCGCCCCUCCUUCUGCCUUGCUCAAGCUCACAGUCCAUGGCCGGGCGGGGCUGCCCUCCCCACCCAGGACGAGGCAUGCACUCCGGUGUCCAUGGCUGGAGCUGGGCUCCUUCUCAGUCUCCGGUUUGAAACAGUGGUCAGGUGGUUGGAAGUGGGUGGCUUAGAGGGCCUGAUCUGGCCAGGCGUGGGAUCCUGACGGCAGCAUAAGCAGGCCCCCAUGUUGAGCUGUGACCGUCCAUCCUCAUGCUUGGAGGAAGCUGGCCUGCAGCCUGGGAGCCUUCCUUUGUGCCCUGACCACCCCCACAUCCCCAAAGGUCAGUUUCAGCCCCAUUUCCUGGCUCUGGGCCUGUGCAGCAGCAGUGGAUACUGGGAAUGUCCCCACCUGACCGACACCUGGGAGCUGACAUCUGGGCCCUGGGAGGCAGCAGCAGCACAGCCUGGGCCUUCUGUCAGGGUGCUGCCCGGCAGUCUCAGCGGAGCUGCGUGUGGUGCUUGGUGCCCAUAACUGGCGUGAGCUCUCUCUGUGCCUGACUCCUCCACCCUCAGGAGCCUCGUGGGGAAGUGGAAGGACCAGGCCGUGUGGCUGGCCCCAGUGUCUGUGCUGCCUGGGGGCCCAGCAGGAAGGGUGUUCUGGGAGCUACCUGGAGGCCUUGGAAGGGCAGGAGCCUGCUGCUGUCCAGGCCUUGAGGGAGGGCCGCAAGUCACAGGAGACAGGACACAGGUCUCAGGACUCGGUCACCCCAGGCCCCACCAACCAGGGUGGGGCAGGACUCGCUUUCACUCUGAGUCACGUGGAGCCCCUGGGAGGUUUUGAGCAGACCGGUGACUUGAUCCGACUUGGUUUUAACAGGAUCACCCUGCGGUGCGGGCUAGGCGGUCCUUGCGGGGCAGAGCAGGGAGCCCUGCUGGGAGGGCUUCAUGGAAAUCCUUGCAAGUGGUGGUGGCGAGGGGCAGUGCUGCCACGCUUUGGCCUGGGGCUGCCCUCCGCACCAGGGUUGCAGCCUGGGGCUGUGAGCACCGGGUCGGUGAGGUGGAGAGGCACCCGCUCACCUCAGGAGGGCAUAGAAGAGGGUGGGUGUGAGGGGCUUCCCUGGAUGAGGCCCUGGCACAGGUGGGCGCCCCAGAGACGGGGCACGUUCUCUCGUGCUGGCAUGCUUGGUGGGUGAGCUGUGUUGCGUGUAGUUUGAAGCCCUUUCCUCUCUGGGGUGGGGUGGGAGGAAGUGAGGUUACACGCAGGGUGCUGACGACAUUGAGCAUCCAGCUUGGGGAGGGGGUCCUGGUUUGCAGCAUUUGCCCAUGGCUGUGGUGUAACUGCCCACCGAGGCAGAUUUCAGGGGACCAACCAGAUGUCACCCAGCUCACAAACUUCCCCUAGUCUUGACUGUCUGCCCCGAGCGUCUACAAGUGGCCGGUUCUGGGGCCGGAGCCGGCUCCUCCCAUGGCAGAGCUGCUGCCUGUGCUCCGAGGGGAGCCUCCAGCCGUGACCUGUCUAACUGUCAGUUACACGACUGCAGGAAAGGCCCAAGUGGCAGCAAGCUGUCGCCUGGUUGGGCCCGGAAAUGGGACGUCGCGCUUUCUCAGGGAGCGUAGAAGCAGCCAGGGCCUCUCCAAGCCGCUGCUGUGACAGAAAGUGAGUGAGCUGCCGGAGGAUGUCCACCGCCACGACAGUCGCCCCCGCGGGGAUCCCGGCGACCCCGGGCCCUGUGAACCCACCCCCCCCGGAGGUCUCCAACCCCAGCAAGCCCGGCCGCAAGACCAACCAGCUGCAGUACAUGCAGAAUGUGGUGGUGAAGACGCUCUGGAAACACCAGUUCGCCUGGCCCUUCUACCAGCCCGUGGACGCAAUCAAAUUGAACCUGCCGGAUUAUCAUAAAAUAAUUAAAAACCCAAUGGAUAUGGGGACUAUUAAGAAGAGACUAGAAAAUAAUUAUUAUUGGAGUGCAAGCGAAUGUAUGCAGGACUUCAACACCAUGUUUACAAAUUGUUACAUUUAUAACAAGCCCACAGAUGACAUAGUGCUAAUGGCCCAAGCUUUAGAGAAAAUUUUUCUACAAAAAGUGGCCCAGAUGCCCCAAGAGGAAGUUGAAUUAUUACCCCCUGCUCCAAAGGGCAAAGGUCGGAAGCCGGCUGCGGGAGCCCAGAGCGCAGGUACACAGCAAGUGGCGGCCGUGUCCUCUGUCUCCCCAGCGACCCCCUUUCAGAGCGUGCCCCCCACCGUCUCCCAGACGCCCGUCAUCGCUGCCACCCCUGUACCAACCAUCACUGCAAACGUCACGUCGGUCCCAGUCCCCCCAGCUGCCGCCCCACCUCCUCCUGCCACACCCAUCGUCCCCGUGGUCCCUCCUACGCCGCCUGUCGUCAAGAAAAAGGGCGUGAAGCGGAAAGCAGACACAACCACUCCCACGACGUCGGCCAUCACUGCCAGCCGGAGUGAGUCGCCCCCGCCGUUGUCAGACCCCAAGCAGGCCAAAGUGGUGGCCCGGCGGGAGAGUGGUGGCCGCCCCAUCAAGCCUCCCAAGAAGGACCUGGAGGACGGCGAGGUGCCCCAGCACGCAGGCAAGAAGGGCAAGCUGUCGGAGCACCUACGCUACUGCGACAGCAUCCUCAGGGAGAUGCUAUCCAAGAAGCACGCGGCCUACGCCUGGCCCUUCUACAAGCCAGUGGAUGCCGAGGCCCUGGAGCUGCACGACUACCACGACAUCAUCAAGCACCCGAUGGACCUCAGCACCGUGAAAAGGAAGAUGGAUGGCCGAGAGUACCCAGACGCACAGGGCUUUGCUGCUGAUGUCCGGCUGAUGUUCUCGAAUUGCUACAAAUACAAUCCCCCAGACCACGAGGUUGUGGCCAUGGCCCGGAAGCUCCAGGACGUGUUUGAGAUGAGGUUUGCCAAGAUGCCAGAUGAGCCCGUGGAGGCACCGGCGCUGCCUGCCCCCGCGGCCCCCAUGGUGAGCAAGGGCGCUGAGAGCAGCCGUAGCAGUGAGGAGAGCUCUUCGGACUCAGGCAGCUCGGACUCGGAGGAGGAGCGGGCCACCAGGCUGGCGGAGCUGCAGGAGCAGCUGAAGGCCGUGCACGAGCAGCUGGCCGCCCUGUCUCAGGCCCCAGUAAACAAACCAAAGAAGAAGAAGGAGAAGAAGGAGAAGGAGAAGAAGAAGAAGGACAAGGAGAAGGAGAAGGAGAAGCACAAAGUGAAGGCCGAGGAAGAGAAGAAGGCCAAGGUGGCUCCGCCUGCCAAGCAGGCUCAGCAGAAGAAGGCUCCUGCCAAGAAGGCCAACAGCACGACCACGGCCGGCAGACAGCUGAAGAAAGGCGGCAAGCAGGCAUCUGCCUCCUACGACUCAGAGGAAGAGGAGGAGGGCCUGCCCAUGAGCUACGAUGAAAAGCGCCAGCUUAGCCUGGACAUCAACCGGCUGCCCGGGGAGAAGCUGGGCCGGGUAGUGCACAUCAUCCAAUCUCGGGAGCCCUCGCUCAGGGACUCCAACCCCGACGAGAUAGAAAUUGACUUUGAGACUCUGAAACCCACCACUUUGCGGGAACUGGAGAGAUAUGUCAAGUCUUGUUUACAGAAAAAGCAAAGGAAACCGUUCUCAGCAAGCGGGAAGAAACAGGCAGCCAAGUCGAAAGAGGAGCUAGCUCAGGAAAAGAAGAAGGAGCUGGAAAAGCGUCUGCAGGAUGUCAGCGGGCAGCUGAGCAGCAGCAAGAAGCCCGCCCGGAAAGAGAAGCCCGGCUCAGCACCCUCAGGGGGCCCGUCCAGGCUCAGCAGCAGCAGCUCCUCCGAGUCUGGGAGCAGCAGCUCCAGCGGGUCCAGCUCUGACAGCAGUGACUCAGAAUGAACUGGCUUCGGACAGAACAGGACAGAUGGAUGUCGCACACGCCGAGACUCUGCCGUACCCCUCUGUGGUUCAUAUUACUACUUCUGUUCCAUGGUGUGCAGGUCUGCUUCUUAAUUCAGUGUUAUGAUAUCUUCCAGUUUUUGCUUUCAUAGGUCAGAGAUCUAUCUUGUGUGUGCGUUAGACUUGAUGAGAAGGUGUGAACUCUGCAGAAAGUCUCUUCUUCAUCACUGAAUUCAGUCACUUGGAGAUGACAACUUCAAAUGCUAACCCGAUGACCCCAGAAAACCGUGUGAGAUUCGUACCGAAGAACCUUGUGGAAUCCCUUUGCUUAGGCCCAACCUGGUCGAUAGCUCGAGAAAGAAUUUUUUCCAAGGAAAUGUCUCGGAUAUGGGUACUGUAUUUGAAAGCUGUUAGCUUUGUCAACACGCAUUGUCCUUGUCAUUUGGGCCCCGAGCUCUGACCCUCGUGUCUGACGCGGCCACCUCUUUCUGGAGGGGCUGAGGACAGAUGUGCCUGCUUGUGGAGACCAGGCUGGGCCUAAGCGAAGGGUCAUCGCAGCCCCAGCCCGGAGCGUGGAGCCCUUGGGGGGUGGUCGGGUGGGAUGUGCGUUCUCCGCUCGUGGUGAUGUCAGGAGCUCCUCGGAGGGAACAGAGCGGCUGUGUAUGCAGCCUGCAGGUUUCCAUACACUGAAGCUUUUACCUCAACUUUAAAAAAAAAAAAAGAAGAAAAGAUUUAAAAAAAAAAAAAAAGGAGACUUUUUUUGUAAGGUUCGGCAAUUUUCUACGGAAGUCCAGCCCGCUGUGAGUCCCCGCCUGGCUAGCGCUGCCCCUGCUGCUGCUGCCGCGCCACCCUUGGGAACCACUUCCCGAGCUUAUGUGUAUAUAAAUAGUUAUUUAUUAACAUCAUUGGUCAUUUUUAAAAAAAAGAAAAUAAGAAAAAACCGCAGAAGAAAUGCAUUCACACAGUCGCAGAGAUGCAGGCCUUGCCAGUGGUGUGCCGGGCGCGGGUCCUGUCUGGCGGCGGCCUGUCGUCUCCAGGUGCUAACUCCUGCCACCGCGCGGUGCUCACCCACGUCUGUUCGCGCGCUCGCCCCUGGGUUUGUUGGGUUUUUUGGUUUUUUUCUUUGUGGUUUUUUUUUUUUUUUUUUUUUGUAUGAAACUUGGAGGCUUACAGGUAUAGACAGCUUUCAGCUACAGCACAUUCUAAUUUUUUAUUUUGUUUAGUUCUUUUGUAUUCACUUCUGGUCUCUUUAAGACUGUUUUAAAAGAAAUCAAUUUAGGGAACCCCAGUUAUAUAAUAUAAACUUUGUAAUCUGAGAGAAAAAAUGUAUAGUAAAUCUAAGUCUUGAUUUUUAACUUUCUAUUGUAAAAAAUAAUAAUAUACAGAGUUUAAUAGAAGGUGAUGUUUUGGUUUUGUUUUCCCAGAGGCUGCCAUAUGGUCUUUGAGUACGGGGAUGUCCCAAACUGGCCCACCAAUGAGCAUGGCGGCUCCGGCCAGGAAUGCCAGAGUUAGCCUCCCAGGCUUGCGGGUGGACAUGCCUGCUCCCUGCCAGCCUCCAGUGGCCUGGCCAGGCCCUCCCGAGCCUGUCUGCCCUCCCCAGGGGUGGAGGAGUCUCUGGGCCCCAGGAGGAUUCCCUCCCGGAGACUCGCACGGUGCUCCCUGCUCACGCGUUGUCACAGUUAGUCCGGAAAUGACUGAAACCAGGCAUUCUCCCGGACCUCAGCGUGGGGGAGCCUCCAGGCAGACGCUGGGUAUGGAGCUGUGGUGUGGUCUGUCCUGUAUGGUGGCCAGUGCUUUCUGCCAGCAUUUCUGGAUGGAUAUAGGGACUAUCAUUAGUAUCCUAAUACACGGUGAUUUUAAAACAACCAUAAAAUUGAUUCAGAGUCCACUGACCCUUACAGAUGUAGGUAUACCCUUACUGGAGAGGGAACUCUGAUGAGGAGAUGCUGGUAAAUUAUCAUUUUUUAAAUUGCUGGUGAGUCUGACACUUGGUGAGUUUUCAGCCAGUUUGUUAAACUUUUAAUUAAGUUUUGUUUAUAAUAAAAAUAUAAAUGGAUUUGAAAGUUUCCAUUUUUUAAAGUUACCCUCGUUUUCAAAGGUAUUUUCUAAACAGAUCUUUAAUGGACUAUUUAAACCGAAUUUAAGGAAUUCACACACGACAGUUGACAGGUCUUCACGCAGGCUGGUUGGUAACGUGCUGCCAGCACAGGGCUGGGUGAUACGUACACCCUAAGCCGGGGGUGCCUGGGGCUGGGGGGCGCUCCUUGCAAUGCCCCUCCAGCCACAGGGCAGUGAGGUGCUGCCUGUGUGAGCCGUCGGGGGAGCGGCCGGCUGUGGGGGCAGCGCAGCAGGAGCAUCGUGGGGCCUUUCCUUCUCGGCUGGUUCUCUGUGACGGUGGCGUCGGCUCGCCUCUGCUCCUUUCAUCUAGAAAGAAGCCACUGACCCUGACAGCCCACGGCGGGUACACUGAGCAGCUGCAUUGGUGCUGUCACUUUUUUAAGGCUUUCUGUCCAGACUUCAACACUGGUUUCUUUUCAGAGUUUCGAAGGAUUAAUGACUUCCUCAGCGCCCUUGCUGGCGGGCUGAGGGUGACAGUCACGUCCGUUUCUUCUGUAUUAGAAGGCUGCGGUGAUUCAAUUAGAUUGUCCCACUGCUGAGACCUGUAGGGCAGCUUCUAACAUGCUUUUUUCAAGGGGAGAGGAGUAGUGACAAGUCGUGUGUCGGAAUUGGAUUUGAGAACACUCUGAAUGACCCCUGGAGGCCGAGGGGGCAGGCUUCGGGCGUGAACUGAACUCCAGACCCCUCUUUGUGUUGGGCAGUGUCAUCUUGCUUACAAACUGUAAGACACAUUUUUUUGUGUGUUUGUUUUUGUUGUUGUUCUUUUGCAGCACUCACGCCUCUGACAGUCUUUUGGGAAAGAGUAACACCCACAUACAGAAUUUGUCACAUCCAGAGUAGCACUGUUCCUUAAUACUGGCAUAAUGCUUCCAGGAAGUUUUUCUUUUUUAUAUUUAAAAUGUUACUUUUCUGUAUGAUGUGCAUGCAAGUUUACCGUAACUUUUCUUAAACUUUUUAGUGCCGUUUCUAGUAUAUUCCUGUAAAUGUCAGUUACUGAAAAUGAGUCCAAUGUAAGUAGUUUAGCUUGUUUAUUGCAAUGCUGGCCUCAACACAACAGAAUAAAAAUGGUAGAAAGUACUCUUUGAUGUUUCUGGUAAUCAUGGACCCUUCUCCUGGGGCAUUUGUUUUGUUUUCAUAAUAAAAAGCAAAAAAAAAAAAAAAAAAAAA